CAGAGCCGGUUCUUUGAGUGCCAGCUUUCAAAUAGAUACAUUAAUCUCAACCUAGUUUUAUCAAUUAUUUAUUAAUAAGCACUCCCAAAGUGCACAAAAGUUCUUAAGUUCUUUCUAAUUCUGAUCUUGUUUAUACUCUUCUUUGGUAAGGUUUCUUUGGCAAGGUGAAAAAUAACCUGACACAUAGAGAUGGGAUUGCUGGAUUCUAGUUUUGUUUGUCUGUUACUAGCUUCCUAAAAAGGUCUCAGAAGUCCCUUUGUUUGCUCAUCUGUCAUAUGAGAUAAGAGUAUUUGCCUUCUCAUCCUAAAGGUUACGUAGAUUUAAAAAGUUAUUCUGGGAGAAUUAGAAGCACUUUCAGUUGAAAGACAUUAUUUUACAGCAGUCCUCUAUCAUAGAUAGGUACUGAAAUAUCUAUUAUUGAUGCGAUUUAAGUAUUAAUGGCAAGACUUAUAGAAAAUUAUUAAAAAAGUUUGAAUAAUUUAUAUAACAUGAGGUACUCCAAUUAAUCAAAUGGUAUGCCUCUACUUAGAUCUUUUCGGACCUGUUUAUAGUUUCUACAAGGGCAAAUGGAGAUAGCAUGGUUAAGGAUGUCAUUCAUAGUGUUAUUGGAAAGGACAAUAGUAUAUCAUUGUUAAAUAUCAUUUAGUCUGGCCUUUUUGUUUGACUGAUGAAGCUGAGACCCAGAAAGUGUAAAAGACACAUCUGAGGUCCAACAAUGUCUGUGGUAGAACUAGAGGCCGCCACCCGGGUUUCUCACUCCCCAUCCAAGUUUCUCUACACUUAGAGGGUGCGUUGUCUUACUCUCAGUUUCCCGCUUUAGUCAGAAAAGAUCACUGGCUCUGGAUUCUCUUCAUUCCUUCUUGUUGGCAAGUGGGGUUGGGAGGAGGGAAGUGAGCAAAAGGCAGGCCUUAAAGAAAUUGACAUGUCUUCUGCAGCUUAUGUUUUUUCUUCCACUUUUAUCUGGAGUGUUCUGAACUCCAACAUGAAGUGACUUGAAUGUGAGAAGCGACUCAGUCAGUGAUGGCAUUCAGGGAAGCUGCUUUUAAAACCACCUAGGUUGGUUCAUACAUAGCAAGCUGCUGGCACUUCCUUAGCCCCAUACCCCCUGAUUGGUCCCCACCCCAUCCUGCCAUCGGCCUGUUUACCAUGUUGGCUUUUUGGUGAAGAGACUGCACAGGGCAGAAAAAUUAUUAAAAUCCUUCCUGGCUUUUUUCCUGAACAAUCCUGAAUGCUACUUCAGCAAUUAUAGGAGGAAAAAUAAAAUUAUUUUCCCCUUGCUUCCUAUAUAAUUUAGGACCACUAGAAAACUCUGUGAUCCCAAGUUAUUCUGUUUCUCUCUGAUACCAAUUUUUCUGAUAACAGAAAAUUAUCCCUGUGUAUACUUUAGUAAAGGGUCUGAGGGUGGUUUUUCUAGAGACUGAGAAUGACCCAGAGUUGUUUCAGUUUGAAUCAUUUCUAUUGUUCUGCUUCCACAUUUCACUGACUCUUUCCUCUGUCAUCUCCAUUUUGUCCUUAAGCCCAUUCAGUGAAUUAAAAAAAUUCAGAUACUGUAUUUCUGUUCAAAAAUUUCCACUUAAAUUUUUUUUUUCAGUUUCUCUUCUGAGAUUUACUGUUUUCCCCUUCAUUUUGAGCAUAUUUUCUUUUUUUUUUUUCUUUUUUUGAGACGGAGUCUCGUUCUGUCGCCAGGCUGGAGUGCAGUAGCUGAAUCUCGGCUCACUGCAAGCUCUGCCUCCCGGAUUCAGGCGAUUCUCCUGCCUCAGCCUCUCAAGUAGCUGGGACUACAGGCGCGCGCCACAACACCCGGCUAAUUUUUGUAUUUUUAGUAGAGACGGGGUUUCACCAUGUUGGUCAGAAUGGUCCCGAUCUCCUGAUCUCGUGAUCCGCCUGCCUCGGCCACCCAAAGUGCUGAGAUUACAGGCAUGAGCCACCGUGUCCGGCCUUGAGCAUAUUUUCUUUUACCUCAUUGAUCUUAGUUAUAAUAGCUCUGUUAAUAUCUUUGUCUGAGAAUUUCAGCAUCUGGGUUGUCUUGGAGUUGCCCUCUGCUGAUUGUCUUUUCCUUUGCAAAUUGCAAAUGGGUUUAAUUUUUCUAGGUGUUUUUUGUUUGUUUGUUUGUUUUUGUUUUGUUUUGUUUUGAGACAGGGUUUCACUCAGUCGCCCAGGCUGGAGUGCAGUGGUGUGGACAUGGCUCACUGCAGCCUUGACUACUGGGCUGAAGUGAUCCUCCUGCCUCAGCCUCUCAGGUAGCUGGGACCACAGGCAUGUAUCACCACACCUGGCUAAUUUUUUUAAAUUUAUUUUCAUUUUUUGUAGAGACAGUGUCUCACUGUGUUGCCCAGGCUGGUCUCAAAAACACUUUGGGCUCAGAUGAUCCUCCUGUCUUGGCCUCCCAAAGUGCCAGGAUUACAGGCAUGAGCCACCGUGUCCAGAUGCUUUUUCUAGUUCUUUAUGUAAUUUGGAAUUGUAUUCUUCACACUGUGAAUGUUGUAUUGUGGAGACUUUGGUUUCUGUUGAUGUUUUUAAUUUAGUAGACAAUAACUCAGACUCAAAACUGCAAACUCUGUCACACCUGCAGUGGGUCGCAGUUCAAAUUUCAGUUCAGUUCUUUUCUCUUUAACUGAGGUCUUUGGAUUCUGCCCUAUGCUUGCAUGGCUCAGGGUUCAGCCAGAGACUGGGUAGAAUUUACACACAGAACCUGAGACUCUCCUUUUCUAGCUCUUUUUUUUCUUACUUCCAUGAUCUGUGGCUGCUCUGGGCUAUUUCUUCAGGACAGAAAGCCUAGGGUUUGUUUUUUGAUUGGAACUUCAGCUAGACCAGCCUCAGGCUAGAGAUCCAAAAAUGAGGAGUUCAUUCCAUGUCAGCCCUUUCUUCCAACUUUCAACUUAUUUUCAAAAUCUGCCAGCCCUUGUUCACUUCAGAUAGUUUUUGUGUUUUAUCCAGAGUAUAGUUGUUGUCUGUGGGAGGGUCAUACUGAAAGCAGAAUUUCUUACUGACAUUUUUAUCUAUUAUCAAAGUGUUUGGGGGACAAAAAUGUUCACUUGAGCUUGUUUUGUAAGCUUGGGCAAGUCUCCUUUCCUCUCUGGGACCCACUUGCUCCUCUGGGAAAGGAGGUGGUUGGACUCUGUGAUCUGUAAGGAUCCUUCAGUCUCUGCUUCUAGGCAGACAGACACGUACACACAUACUACCACCACUAUCACCACCAACAGUAACAGAAACAAUAAGUGCCAGAAGAGAUGCUUGAGGGAAGUGAUGAGGAUGGAUCUGUCAUGGUGGAAAGCUCUCUGAAGCAGCAUCACUAAGGAAUUUGAGGAUGUUUACAGUCAUCCUCUUGUUUUGGGGACAGAGGGCAAGUACGCUGAGGAAGCAAGAAGUAAAUGGCAUUCAGAAGAAAGAAAUCAGUUACUGCUUACUUCUACCCCUUAGAAAUAUGAGAGAACGUAGACAGUUGAAAACAAAUCAGGAUUAGCUGGAGUUCCUCUUUCCCUUUGGCAGUGCAUUCUGUCUUGUUUUGAAGAGAAAAGCCCCUGGGCCUUAGUAACAUGUCAGCAAAUUUGGCAGUAGGUGGUAGGUGCUGGGACAGUAGAUUUUAGCAGGGGCGCUGCUAUCACUGUUAGGGCUGCAGAGACCUUAGGGGAGAUAGACCAGAUUUAUGUGACCAUUUCUUAGAGUUCAGAAUUUUUAUGUAGGAGAGGUUUUAGGCUAUGCAGAAGAAGAUGAGUGUGUGUGUGGGGGGGCGGUGUUUGUGUGUGGGUGUUGUGUGUGUAAGGUGGGUGGGGAGGGGGAAAGAGACAGGUGGUGAUGGGGUAGGACGGAAAGUCUGUGGAACUGUCCUAAAACUAUUUGAAUACCAAUCACACUUACUUUAACUUCCAUUGAUUAUUUUUUAAAAGCAGAGGGUGGAGAGCUAAAGCUUCCCCCACAUCCACCUAAGCUAUCUCUUGGGUGCCGCCUUGGUAUAGAUCGUUUUUAAAAUUAUUUUUAAAUAUAGAGCGUCACUCUGUCAUCUAAGCUGGAGUGCAGUAGGACAACUGUGGCUCACAGCAGCCUCAAACUUCUGGGCUCCAGGUGAUCCUCCCGUCUCAGUCUCCCAAGUAGCUAGGACUAUAGGUGUGCAUCACCAUGCCCAGCUAAUUAAAAUUUUUUUUUUUUUGUAGAGAUGGGGGCCUUGCUUUGUUGUUGUCCAGGCUGUUCUUGAACUCCUGGGUUCAAGCAAUCCUCCUGCCUUGGCCUCCCAAAGUGCUGGGAUUAUAGGCAUGAGCCACUGUGCCUGGCCUAGAUCCUUUUUUAUACUUAUUUUCUAGCUGUUUUUAUUAUCAGUAACUUUUUUUUUUUUUUUUUUUUUGAGACAGCGUCUCACUGUGUCGCCCAGGCUGGAGUGCAGUGGCGCGAUCUGGGCUCACCACAAACUCCGCCUCUUGGUUUGAAGAGGUUCUCUUGCCUCAGCCUCCUGAGUAGCUGGGAUUAUAGGCACAUGUCACCAUGCCCAGCUAAUUUUUGUAUUUUUAGUAGAGAUGGGGUUUCACCAUAUUGGCCAGGGUUGUCUUGAACUCCUGACCUCAGGUGAUCUGCCCGCCUUGGCCGCCCAAAGUGCUGGGAUUACAGGCGUGAGUCACCGUGCCUGGCCGAUACUAUCAGUAACUCUUCUCUUUGGGAGGCCAAGGUGUGAAGAUUGCUUGAGGUCACGAGUUUCAGACCAGCCUGGGUGACAUAGUGUGACCCCAUCACUACAAAAAAAAAUUCUUUUCAAAUUUUAUUCUCUUGAGGCUUGAGUUACUACUGUUCCCCUCAUCUUUUAAGCUGUUUUUAAAAAACUCUCAUUAUUUGUCCAUUGUAAUUCUAGCCGCCUUGCUCUCUGGGAAGAUAGAGGCAGGGAUGGGUGUGUGUGUGUGUGUGUGUGUGUGUGUGUAUGUGUGCGCGUUCAUGCAUGCGCGCAGGUGCAGGUAUGUGUGCAUGUGUGCAUGUUUUGGUGGAGGUGUGGAAGUUGGAUUAAAGGGACCAAUAGUCUUGGAAGGCAGUCACAAGGUGGCUUGCAGGGAUGUGUAAGGGAGGCAGUUGUGAUGAAAGAAGGGAGGAUAGUUUGUAAGAUCAUGUACAAAAGCUUUAGGUUUACCACUAGCUUAGAAGCUACCUUUCCAUUUUCCUCAAGAGUAAGAUAACACAAGAAGUUUGACCCAGAUCUUCCAUCUGUAGUAGCUCUUCUCUAAUUUUAGGGGUAAGAUUCAAUGGGAUGGUAGGCUUUUCAACUCUCCUGUAGAAGCCUGCUUGUUUCAAAACUGGAGGGGGACAUUGAAUAAACCUGAGUAUUGUGUGCCUGUAUUUUGACUGCGACCUAUCAGAUGAGAUCAGGUCAAGAGACAACUGCCUUUGAAAGAGAGUGAGUGACUGUUUCCAAAACAGCAAGCAUAGGGAGAGCCGCCGGAAGUAUUGACGGAAAGCUUGAAUUACCUACAUGAUUGAUGAUGGUCUCCAGCUGUCAAAGAAGAUUGUGGUUGCCAAGAGAAAGGUAACCAUUUCUCAUCCCCUUGAGUGGAAUUGGAUGCCUCUAGGAGCCCACAUUGGCUGGCAGUAGACAUGGCCGAAUUUACAAGCUACAAGGAGACGGCCUCCAGCCGCCACUUGCGGUUUAAGCUACAGAGUCUAAGCCGCCGCCUUGAUGAGUUGGAGGAAGCCACAAAAAACCUCCAGAAAGCAGAGGAUGAACUCCUGGAUCUCCAGGACAAGGUGAUUCAGGCAGAAGGUAGCAACUCCAGCAUGUUGGCGGAGAUUGAAGUGCUGCGCCAGCGGGUGCUGAGAAUUGAAGGCAAAGACGAGGAAAUUAAGAGAGCAGAGGAUCUGUGUCGUCUGAUGAAGGAGAAACUUGAAGAGGAAGAAAACCUCACCCGGGAGCUGAAAUCUGAGAUUGAGCGGCUUCAGAAACGAAUGGCUGAAUUAGAGAAGCUAGAAGAGGCCUUCAGCAGGAGUAAGAAUGACUGUACCCAGCUGUGUCUGAGCCUGAAUGAGGAGAGAAAUCUGACCAAGAAAAUCUCCUCUGAGCUGGAAAUGCUCAGAGUCAAAGUGAAAGAACUAGAAUCUUCUGAGGACCGCCUGGAUAAAACUGAGCAGAGUUUAGCGUCAGAGUUAGAAAAGCUGAAAUCAUUAACUCUGAGCUUUGUAAGUGAGAGAAAAUACUUGAAUGAAAAGGAGAAAGAAAAUGAGAAAUUGAUAAAAGAACUCACUCAAAAACUAGAGCAGAACAAAAAAAUGAACCGAGAUUAUACAAGGAAUGCUUCUAAUCUGGAAAGAAAUGACCUACGGAUUGAGGAUGGCAUCUCUUCCACACUGCCGUCCAAAGAAUCAAGAAGGAAGGGUGGUCUGGACUACCUAAAGCAGGUAGAGAAUGAAACAAGAAACAAAUCAGAAAAUGAAAAGAACCGCAAUCAGGAAGACAACAAAGUCAAAGACCUUAACCAAGAGAUUGAGAAACUUAAGACACAAAUCAAACACUUUGAAUCGUUGGAAGAAGAGCUUAAGAAAAUGAAGUCCAAAAAUAACGACCUUCAGGAUAAUUACCUAAGUGAACAAAAUAAAAACAAAUUAUUAGCCAGCCAACUGGAGGAGAUAAAGCUACAAAUCAAGAAACAGAAAGAGUUAGAAAAUGGAGAGGUAGAAGGGGAAGAUGCUUUCCUGUCCAGCAAAGGCAGACAUGAGAGGACUAAGUUUAGAGGCCACGGAAGUGAAGCUUCUGUGUCCAAGCACACAGCGCGGGAACUGUCUCCUCAGCAUAAGCGGGAACGACUCCGGAACAGGGAGUUUGCUCUCAACAAUGAAAACUAUUCUCUGAGCAACAGGCAGGUUUCUUCUCCCAGUUUCACCAACAGGAGGGCAGCAAAAGCUUCUCACAUGGGGGUGAGUACAGACAGUGGGACUCAGGAGACAAAGAAAACUGAAGACCGGUUUGUACCCGGCUCCUCCCAGAGCGAAGGGAAGAAGUCUAGGGAGCAGCCCUCAGUGCUGAGUCGCUACCCCCCGGCUGCUCAGGAGCACAGUAAAGCGUGGAAGGGGACUUCCAAGCCAGGCACCGAGAGCGGACUGAAGGGAAAAGUGGAGAAGACAACACGAACGUUUAGUGACACCACCCAUGGAUCUGUUCCCAGUGACCCAUUGGGUAGAGCUGACAAGGCUUCUGACACCUCCUCUGAGACUGUCUUUGGCAAGAGGGGACACGUGCUUGGCAACGGAAGUCAAGUAACUCAGGCUGCAAACUCUGGCUGUUCUAAGGCCAUUGGAGCCCUGGCCUCAUCUCGAAGAUCCUCCUCAGAAGGGCUCUCUAAAGGCAAAAAGGCUGCCAAUGGCCUUGAGGCUGAUAACAGUUGCCCGAAUUCCAAGGCUCCUGUUCUAUCGAAGUAUCCUUAUAGCUGUAGAAGCCAAGAGAACAUCCUUCAGGGAUUUUCAACCUCACAUAAAGAAGGGGUUAAUCAACCUGCAGCAGUUGUGAUGGAAGACAGCAGUCCGCAUGAAGCCUUGAGGUGUCGAGUCAUCAAAUCCAGUGGCAGAGAGAAGCCAGACUCAGAUGAUGACUUGGACAUAGCAUCUCUUGUUACUGCCAAGUUGGUAAAUACAACCAUCACUCCAGAGCCAGAGCCCAAACCACAGCCUAACUCUAGAGAAAAGGCUAAAACCCGAGGGGCACCUAGAACCUCCCUAUUUGAGAAUGAUAAAGAUGCUGGAAUGGAGAAUGAAUCUGUGAAAUCUGUCAGAGCCUCCACCAAUACCAUGGAGCUCCCAGAUACCAAUGGUGCUGGGGUAAAAAGCCAAAGGCCCUUUAGCCCCAGAGAGGCGUUGCGGUCUAGAGCCAUCAUCAAACCUGUUAUUGUUGAUAAGGAUGUGAAAAAAAUCAUGGGAGGAUCUGGAACAGAGACUACGUUGGAGAAACAGAAACCCGUCUCCAAACCAGGGCCAAACAAAGUGACAAGUAGCAUUACUAUAUAUCCAUCUGACAGCAGCAGCCCCAGAGCUGCUCCGGGUGAGGCCCUGAGGGAGAGGCACACAUCCACUAGCAAUAUCCAGGUGGGGCUGGCAGAGCUCACAUCAGUUAGCAACCAUGUCAGCUCCCCUUUUGAGCUCUCCAUUCACAAACAUGACAUCACCCUGCAGCUUGCAGAAGCGGAGAGAAUGGCAGAUGGGCCCCUGAAGGACAGGCCAGAAACAGUGGUCUCUCGGAGCAGCAUUAUAAUCAAGCCAUCGGAUCCUGUGGAGAGGAAUAGCCAUGCACCUCCAGCGGAGACAAUCAGGUGGAAAAGCCAUAGUGCCCCUUCAGAAGUGGGCUUCUCAGAUGCCAGACAUGUUACUGUGCGGAAUGCCUGGAAGAGUAGGCGAGACUUGAAAUCUUUAGAAGACCCCCCAACUCGAAUAGGUAAAAACGUGGAAUCUACCAAUAGCAAUGCCUACACCCAGAGGUCUUCCACAGACUUCUCAGAACUCGAACAGCCCAGGUCCUGCCUUUUUGAGCAGGGCACUCGAAGGGUAGGACCAAGUUCAGGGGAUGCCCCUGAGCCCUCCUCCAGAAGGACCCAAAGUAGCCUCACUGUGUCAGAGGUGCUUACCCGUCGGAAUCGGGUAGGAGACACCAUCACUGUCGCAGCCUGGAACCACUCAGCAAGCAUGGAGGAAGAAGGGGAAGACUGUACACUCAGUGUCUACAGGCAACUGCACAACUCCCUGGAUCCGUCUGAACUGCCUGGGAAGCAGGGGCUGCCAGAGUCUGGGCGAGUACGGGCCGAGGAACGAUUACGGCCAACCAGGCCCUGUGCUGAGGAGAACUGAGCCCGCUGGGUGUCUGUUGUCUGCCCUCUGCUCCUGCUUCUCAGCUCUUCCACCGUCCUGCCCCACGAAGGAUCCAAGGCCAGUUAACCAGGCAAGACACAAGCCUUGGCUGGAAAACUGUGGUAGAGCCGGGCUGUGGCUCAGGUAAUUUUUGCCAUUUGGCCAGAGGGAAUCAGAGACUACAAGCUGGACAGUCACCCAGGCCCAACCUUCCCCAAUGCACGAGUCCUCUCUCUCUCCUUGUCCCUGUCCACCAAGUAGUUGGACCAUUCUGGCCCCCAAACAAGGGAAGAUAAAGUCCCCAGCACACAGCAGGAGUCAAAAAUUCUUCUCGGCUCCUUGGUGGGUUGUUUCUGGAUCCUAGGGCAGCCUCUGUCUGUGUGGUUAAUGUUCUGGUUUCUCAGUCUCCUCACUAUAUCCACUUCACUCCUCAUUUGCCCAAUGGGCUCAAGUACCCCAUAAGAUUUACCAGCCAUCAGCUCUAUCUAGGGGGCUUUCAUUUCUUUCCCCUUGGAGUUCUUUUCUUCAGACUUAAAGCAGAAAGGGGUCUGUGCUGCCUCUAAAGGAUUAUGAGACUACCCUUUAGGUUGAAGUUUGACCUGGCUCCUGGCUUACCAGUCUCCUGGAAGCAGAGCAUGCAGAUACUCAUGCGGAUACCCAUUGGAAUGACAUCAUCCCUCCCCAACCCCAGCUCUCUCUGCUCACCUUCCAAAGGCACCUGGAGGUGCAAGCCUCAUGCAUCUCCUUUCCUGAGCACCAGUAAUGCUGCUGGCAUCGCCUGCUUUCUCUCCAGUGGCUGGAGACUUCAAGCUGACUUCAUUGUUUCCACCUUGGGAAAAUCCCUAGGCUAAGCUGGGCCUGACCCAGCAUCCUCUGCCUUCUAGGAAGUGCCCAGCAAGAGGGAAAGCAGACCCCUUUAGUCACUCCACAAGCAAUAGCUCCAUGAGAGGCAUGGACUGUGAGACUACUCCCUCCUGUUCCUCCUUCUCCAUCCCCCAUGGAGGAGGCAUCGCACUUUACCAAGCUGAUGCAUUCCUACAGAAGUGGGCCCCGGAUUUCUGCAAGUCGACUAUCAUGAUGACUUCGCUGGAGGAAAGGUGAUACGUACAUACGCAUUGAGGGCCUCAGCUUUAUAUAGUUCAAAAUGCAGCAAACUUUUCAGAAAGCCACGUAAAUAAAUUGGUUAGGUUCCUUAUACCAGUCACAUGGGGAAGUUGAAAAGAAUUGUAUAUUCUUGGCAGUGCUUUUUCUUUAGCAUUCUGUCAAUUCAAAGAAGGGAUCCUCUUUCAAAGGCUACCUUUAUGAAGUAGACACUAUUGCCCUCAGAAUGAGAGAACAUUAAACUACCAGUCUGGUAAGCUGGAUUUUUUUCCCCAUGGCUUUACUUCCUUGCUGUGUGACCUUGGGUGAGUCAUUGUCUUCUUGGAGCCUCAGUUUCCCUGUCUGUAAAAUGAGUUCUUUGAAAUGGAUGAUCUCUAAGGGCACCAAAUCUGGUAUUCUAAGGUUCUCCUGUUUUCACCAUCUAUAAUAGUAUGGGAUGAUUUUUGCUUGUGGAAGGUAUCAUCCGUGUGGGUUCUUCCCUCCUGCCCUCAAUUGUUUUUCUGGGCCUUGUUUUUUAGUUUCUGUAUGUUUUAAUCUCAUGGGGAUGAGCUCAGAGAAGCUCCGUGGGCCUGUUUCCCAAUCUGCAAAGUGUGAAGGGAUUAGAUGGGAUGGUCUCUGAGGCUCUUUGUGGCAUCAGCCUUGCCCAGUGCCACACAGUAUCUCCUGGCGUUCUAGGAGUCUAGGUAUUAUGGAAAGUACCCAAGUCUGUGUAUCUCCUGUUCCUGUGCAUCUCCUAUGAAUUUCCUGGCAAGAGGAAGACUCAAGACUUCCUCCAGAGGAAUUUGUCUUCUCUGCCUUCACUCAGCAUGGGAACCAGUGUUCAUCCUGACCUUGUCUGUAUCAGAUUUGGCAGUGAGGAGGCUUGGGGAGCACCUACCUUACUUUCAGGGACAGGAAUCUAUUGCUCAUACUUCUGCUUCCCAGAGUUUUGCCAAUCUAAAGGCAUUGUCAUGUGGCCUGCCUUUCCUGUCCACAUCCCCACCUCUGAUGCUCAAGAUGCUAUUUCCAAGAUCUCUUACUGCUGCUUCUCCUGGCUUACUGGCCAGAAACUAGCUCACUCAAGGCUGCCAUCCUUCACUUGCAGCCUCCCUGCCAUUCUCCUUCACUGGUUGGCAACCUUGAGAGUUCAAAGAAAAUCAACCUCUGUGGUGGUCAACUAAAGGUAUUAGGAAACUAAGUCUGUGGCUCUUCUCUGCUGAUGGAAACAGAAGGGCGCCAAGCCAUGCCUAAAAAGAUCUCGCCAAUAAUUCUUGUCUUUGAGUGUUGGAGCCCUGGAUUCUGGUGCUAUAGCUCCUGGUGCCAAAGUCUGGAUCUUUCCACAUUUCAGCAGCACCAACAUCUGCUGCUACUCAAAAUGUCCUGUUGAAGAGGGACAGCUGUGAUGCCCUUUUGCUGGGGCUGCCAUCUUGAAAUCUGAGUGCAAUAGGAUUUGCUUGUAACAGUUAUUUCAGGAUAUUUUGUUUCUUUAAUCUGCACACUUUCUAGAUAGAUUUUAUUUUUAAGUGUCCUCAGCAUUGCAGAAAAUAACAUUGUAAUAGCAAGUAAAGGCUGGAGGCUGUUUCUCUGGGCUUCAAAUGGCUGGCAAGGCUGGCUCUCAAAUCCCAAAGUUGGGAGGCAUGUUUCUGAAAAGCAACUGAGGUGUGACUGUUUGGACCCAGGCCUCAUCAUCAGGGGUCCUGGAGGAAGCCUCCAAGUAGAGGGGAGACCUGGUAGUUGAAUAGUUGUUUAAUCAAGCCAAAUAGUCCCACUGCCCCCGGUCAACAAACCCACUUUUAUGACAGUUUUCUUCCGCAGCUUGGCUCUUAAAUUUUACUGGCAGGUGUAUGGUUGUUGGAGGGUUCCUAGUGAGUUGGGGGACCUGGCAAUAGAGCUGCUUGGUUGGAGGAAGUGAAGCUGGCUUAGUACCAGCAGCUGAUCUCUUCCACGUGCUGCUGCUUUUUUUGCCACUCUGAUACUAAACCAGAGAAAGCUGCAGGUGGAUAAAGAAGCUGUGGCUGUUUUUUGCUUUUGGGUGGCAAUGAGAAAGAGUCACAGUGUGGGUUAAAGGGAUCUGCAGUGGGGCCAAGGAUGCCACCCCACCCUCAGCUGUAGGCAAGCUUGCACAUAAAUAACCCCCGUCAGUGGAGUGUUCGGGAUGCAGGGGGCACUAUAGUGUUCUUGGACUUGUCGUCCUGGGGCAGUUUUAGUUCUUUAUAUUUAGUGGGUCAGUGCCAAGUGCUACCACUUCCCAAUAAAGGAAUGGGGACCCAGAGGCUGGGUCCCUGGCUACCUUGUUAUGAGGUUUUGUUAUUUCUCUGACAAGAUUGCUUUGGAAAGAGCUGCUUUUAGGGAUUAUUUUUUGAAUACCCCGAGUGGGGAGCAGGGUUCUCCUCAAAGCCUCACAACCAUAGGAUCAUAGGAAAGGGGCCCUAUUUUCCUGCUGCUUCCCAGCUCAGAACAUAUACUGAAUGGAAUGUAUUUUUAAGAGAAUAAAGUCUAUUUUUUUGUAUUUUAAAGAUUGAGAGGGCUAAGAAAGUAGCCCUCAAAUAAACUGUUAUUGCAUUAUAGGCCCCUUUGUUGGGGGCAGCCUGUUGGUCCACACCUACUUGCUCAGGCAGGUGCUCUGGUCUCUCUCACCCCUGCCCCUUAGAGUCUAGGUGCAGCAGCUCCAAGCAUGGGACCAAGGAGGCCAGAACCUGUCGCUGGAAACCAGGGCAAAGCAGUGGCUCAGGGCUCCUUGGGUGCAUGUGUAUCAUUGGAGCUGCCUGUCUGCAUGUAUCCUCUGGCGCGAAUGCUCUCUGUUGGCUCUGCAGUACAAUAUGUAACCAAUAAAGCUCCCUCGUUUCCGUAUACUCUGUGCGAGUCUGUGAUGCCAGUUUUGUCAAUGUCAUCCCUGUGUAUCAUCUGUCUUCUAUGCGUUGGCGCAGCUCUAGUAUAUUUAUUUAUUUCAUUGUGUAAUACUUAAAAUUGGGUAUUUUACCUAACCAAUUACUGAUACUGCAAGGACUGGAAACAUUAACUGCCCUGAUCCUGGUGUGCAGAUUCUUUCCAUUACUGCCACGAAUUCUAAGACUAGGGGGGGAAAAGCCUUCUCCGUUUUCAUCUUCCAGUCAGAUCACCAAUAUAUAUAAUGAUGUCCCUUAACUCACAGUAAGAAAGAAUAAAACCACAUUUAAGGGACAUUACUUGGAUUUGCAGUAACAGUGUUUAUCAUCUAUCUGUCAGUCAGUCAGGAGCCCCUGGGAAGGAACCAGCAUGUAACAUGUUUUUAUCAUCUUAUAUGGCAAAAGGGACUUUGCAGAUAAGGAUGCUGGGAUGAGGCAGAACAUCCUAGAUGAUCCAGGUGGGCCUUAAAUGUAAUCACAGGUAGUAUCCUUUUAAGAGAGAGACAAAAGAUUUGACUACAGGAGAAGGCAAUGUGAUGAUGGAAGCAGAAACUGGAGUUAUGUGCUCUGAGGAUGGAGGAAGGAGCCACGAGCCUUCCCACACCUAGAAGCUGAAAAGAGCAAGGAAAUGAACUGAUCCUCCCUGCUCUGAGAGCCUCUGUAAUGAAUGCAGCCCUGUGUACCCAUUUUAGACUUUAAGCUUCCAGAACUUUCGAAUAGAUUUCUGUUUUUUUAAGAGCCACUAAGUUUGUGGCAAUCUGUUAAACCAGCUGUUACCUAAGCCCUUGAUCCUAUGUAGUGCGCUUCCCAAAAUGUACACCACCACCUUUAGUAGAAUUGGGAAGUUUUAGCACAUACCCAUGGAGGGAAUCAGGAAUAAAGGCAGACUGGUCUCCCAAAGGCUCAGACUUUGUUUCAGCUCUUUUGUGUUCUAUCUUGAAAGUGCAUCCAAAGUUUCCUAAUAACCAUGUUCUUGGCACACCACCACACUCCACCCCCACCCAAGUGAGGAAGCCUAGUCCGACUGACCAGGAAGUCCACUGCUUCUACAGGACCGGCCCCCCUACCUUAUCUUCUGACCUGAUCAAACCAUUUUUCUCUUUUAUAUGAACAUCUUCUUCCUUAUUUAAACAUGGAGAAAACAUGUAUUACUAUUGCCAUAGGAUAAACUUGGCAUUUCCAAAGGAGUAAUGCCCCCAUCUUGUAUGUAACUCCAACUCAAAGGAACAAAAGAGAGGGCCAAUUUUAUAUGAAGUUUUAUUCUCAAAAUAUAAAAAAAAAACAAAAA